CGCCCGCUUCUCGCUGGAGUGCGCACCGAGCGGCAGUGACUUCGCCGCUGCUGUAGUUCCCCGGCUGGAUGCGGUGACUGGUGCCAGUGCUCAGGCGCCCGCUGCCCUUGACCUCCCGCCCCGCGAGCCCUAACUCAGCGCAGGAGGACCGGCUGCCGCCGCCGCCGCCGCCAGGUAGACCAGGCCUGGCUGGGUUAGGCCAGAAGGGUGUCCCUGGCGCAGGUCUCCCGCGGAGGGCAGAACUAGAACCAGGUUCCCGGCCGUUUCCGACCACACGGAUGGGGCGGACCCAUCAGAGCCAAGCACAGUGGGAACUUUCAGAAAGCACUGGUUGAAGGAACGCUGGAAUCCCUGGGACUUACUGCGUAGCAUGUAGUAGUUGCUCCUCUACAAAAGUUUCACCUUAUGAAGUAUAGCAGGCUCUGAUGCUGGUGUCUGGUAGAAGAAGAUUACUCACAGCUCUGCUGCAGGCUCAGAAGUGGCCCUUUCAACCCUCCAGAGACAUGAGACUAGUGCAGUUCCGGGCACCCCACCUGGUGGGGCCUCACUUGGGCCUGGAGACAGGGAAUGGUGGAGGGGUUAUCAACCUCAAUGCCUUUGACCCCACACUCCCAAAGACGAUGACGCAGUUCCUAGAGCAGGGAGAGGCCACCCUCUCAGUGGCAAGAAGAGCCUUGGCUGCCCAGUUGCCAGUCCUACCAUGGUCGGAGGUAACCUUCCUGGCUCCAGUCACAUGGCCAGAUAAGGUGGUGUGUGUGGGCAUGAAUUAUGUGGACCACUGCAAAGAACAGAACGUGCCCGUGCCCAAGGAGCCCAUCAUCUUCAGCAAGUUUGCCAGCUCCAUCGUGGGGCCCUAUGAUGAGGUGGUCCUCCCACCACAGAGCCAGGAGGUAGAUUGGGAAGUGGAGCUGGCCGUGGUCAUUGGAAAGAAAGGCAAGCACAUCAAGGCCACAGAUGCCAUGGCCCACGUGGCCGGCUUCACUGUGGCUCAUGACGUGAGUGCUCGUGACUGGCUAACAAGACGCAAUGGGAAACAGUGGCUGCUGGGAAAAACCUUCGACACCUUCUGCCCUCUGGGCCCUGCCUUGGUGACCAAGGACAGUGUAGCAGAUCCACACAACUUAAAGAUCUGCUGCCGAGUGAAUGGGGAAGUCGUCCAGAGCAGCAACACCAACCAGAUGGUAUUCAAGACAGAGGACCUGAUAGCCUGGGUCUCCCAGUUUGUUACCUUUUACCCAGGGGAUGUCAUCCUAACUGGGACCCCCCCAGGUGUCGGUGUAUUCAGGAAACCUCCUGUCUUUCUCAAGAAGGGGGAUGAAGUCCAGUGUGAGAUUGAAGAACUAGGUGUCAUCAUCAACAAGGUGGUGUGAUGGCUCCUGCACAGGCCCGACAUAGGAUGAGGGCAUCUGCUCCCACUCAGCCUAGCCCAGGGAAAGGCCCAGUGGCAGGUGUGGGCAGGUGCCAGCCCUGCAAGCCGCCUCUUCUCGGUAGAAGGGAGAAGGACAGAGCUCUCUUCAAUAAAUGCGUCGGGUCAAAGCAGCA